GACAUCAAGCAAGUCCCAGUUACAGAAAGAACCCACUGCAGGGCGUCCAGUCACUUGCCCAGUGAAAAGACUGUAAUCAGACAACUUUAAUAAAGGGAGAGCAGGAGAGUGGUGACGAAUUUCCACAUUCCGAACAAGCUUGUCGAAAGAGGAGUGCAGGGAAGGAGCAAGAAUGAGGCACUGGAAGACGGUGAGCGGGGCCUUGCCACAGAAUCCCGGGCCCACCUGCUUUCUCACAGUCGCGACAGCCGGCCCGGAGAAGGGCAGCCCAGCGAAGGGCACGCCCCGCGCGGGUGCCAGGGAGGCCGGCAGGGGCGUCCGCGGUCGCUGCUCACCUGCGCUCCCCGCUGCCCGGCCCAGCCCGCCUCGCCACCGAGUCUGGAAGCCCACACUCACCCCUUUACCCGGGAAACGCGGCCGGAGCCGGCGGCGGGUCGGGAGUCCGAGAUGGUAGAUCCCCCUCCAGGCGCCUCGCUGACAUUUUGUCCCGGACGGAAAACCUCCGCGCGUGCCCCUUAAAGACACAGCGCUGCAUUCACACGUCUGCGGGGAAAGGGGGGCCGUCACGUGUGGCCUUCGCCCGAAAGCGGUAGGGGAGUCGCUCUGAAACCGCCAAGGAUCGCGAGCGACAGAUUUGUGUUGGCCAGGGUUUUAAGAUGACGCAAUAGCUGAGUGUGGUUGAAAUGUAACUAUUGUUUUACAACUUUGCAUUAACCUUCCAAGACCUGAAUUCCCGGGCCUGAGUCUCAGAGCGCGGUUUGCAUCUUUGCAGGCUGUAGGCGCAUGAUGUCACAAGUUAUUGGAAGAAAUCCCUCCAACCUAGGUUGGGACAGAUGAAGGCGGCGCUUAUUGGUGUUCACCAAAACACCAGCAUGGUGUACCAGCUUUGGCUAGAUGAUGCUCAGGAAAACACAGAUCCUGGUGCCGAACAUGAGGACAGGGCAGGCCGAAGGAGAAAGUGGAAGGAGGGGAGCUUCUCUCUCAGCCUCAUCCUUCUGGGCCUGGAUGCUGGAGAGUCAUGAGGUGCUUCAGAGUACUCUGGGUGAGGAGGGAAAGAUGGUGCCCACCACAUGGAGGCCAGCCUAGGUCUUGUAUGAAACCUGUGAGCAGGUGUCUUCUGCGGAGGUGCGCAUCGGGCCCAUGAGACUGACGCAGGACCCUAUUCAGGUUUUGCUGAUCUUUGCAAAGGAAGAUAGUCAGAGCGAUGGCUUCUGGUGGGCCUGCGACAGAGCUGGUUAUAGAUGCAAUAUUGCUCGGACUCCAGAGUCAGCCCUUGAAUGCUUUCUUGAUAAGCAUCAUGAAAUUAUUGUAAUUGAUCAUAGACAAACUCAGAACUUCGAUGCAGAAGCAGUGUGCAGGUCGAUCCGGGCCACAAAUCCCUCCGAGCACACGGUGAUCCUCGCAGUGGUUUCGCGAGUAUCGGAUGACCAUGAAGAGGCGUCAGUCCUUCCUCUUCUCCACGCAGGCUUCAACAGGAGAUUUAUGGAGAAUAGCAGCAUAAUUGCUUGCUAUAAUGAACUGAUUCAAAUAGAACAUGGGGAAGUUCGCUCCCAGUUCAAAUUACGGGCCUGUAAUUCAGUGUUUACAGCAUUAGAUCACUGUCAUGAAGCCAUAGAAAUAACAAGCGAUGACCACGUGAUUCAGUAUGUCAACCCAGCCUUCGAAAGGAUGAUGGGCUACCACAAAGGUGAGCUCCUGGGAAAAGAACUCGCUGAUCUGCCCAAAAGCGAUAAGAACCGGGCAGACCUUCUCGACACCAUCAAUACAUGCAUCAAGAAGGGAAAGGAGUGGCAGGGGGUUUACUAUGCCAGACGGAAAUCCGGGGACAGCAUCCAACAGCACGUGAAGAUCACCCCAGUGAUUGGCCAAGGAGGGAAAAUUAGGCAUUUUGUCUCGCUCAAGAAACUGUGUUGUACCACUGACAAUAAUAAGCAGAUUCACAAGAUUCAUCGUGAUUCAGGAGACAAUUCUCAGACAGAGCCUCAUUCAUUCAGAUAUAAGAACAGGAGGAAAGAGUCCAUUGACGUGAAAUCGAUAUCAUCUCGAGGCAGUGAUGCACCAAGCCUGCAGAAUCGUCGCUAUCCGUCCAUGGCGAGGAUCCACUCCAUGACCAUCGAGGCUCCCAUCACAAAGGUUAUAAAUAUAAUCAAUGCAGCCCAAGAAAACAGCCCAGUCACAGUAGCGGAAGCCUUGGACAGAGUUCUAGAGAUUUUACGGACCACAGAACUGUACUCCCCUCAGCUGGGUACCAAAGAUGAAGAUCCCCACACCAGUGAUCUUGUUGGAGGCCUGAUGACUGACGGCUUGAGAAGACUGUCAGGAAACGAGUAUGUGUUUACUAAGAAUGUGCACCAGAGUCACAGUCACCUUGCAAUGCCAAUAACCAUCAAUGAUGUUCCCCCUUGUAUCUCUCAAUUACUUGAUAAUGAGGAGAGUUGGGACUUCAACAUCUUUGAAUUGGAAGCCAUUACGCAUAAAAGGCCAUUGGUUUAUCUGGGCUUAAAGGUCUUCUCUCGGUUUGGAGUAUGUGAAUUUUUAAACUGUUCUGAAACCACUCUUCGGGCCUGGUUCCAAGUGAUCGAAGCCAACUACCACUCUUCCAAUGCCUACCACAACUCCACCCAUGCUGCCGACGUCCUGCACGCCACCGCUUUCUUUCUUGGAAAGGAAAGAGUAAAGGGAAGCCUCGAUCAGUUGGAUGAGGUGGCAGCCCUCAUUGCUGCCACAGUCCAUGACGUGGAUCACCCGGGAAGGACCAACUCUUUCCUCUGCAAUGCAGGCAGUGAGCUUGCUGUGCUCUACAAUGACACUGCUGUUCUGGAGAGUCACCACACCGCCCUGGCCUUCCAGCUCACGGUCAAGGACACCAAAUGCAACAUUUUCAAGAAUAUUGACAGGAACCAUUAUCGAACGCUGCGCCAGGCUAUUAUUGACAUGGUUUUGGCAACAGAGAUGACAAAACACUUUGAACAUGUGAAUAAGUUUGUGAACAGCAUCAACAAGCCAAUGGCAGCUGAGAUUGAAGGCAGCGACUGUGAAUGCAACCCUGCUGGGAAGAACUUCCCUGAAAACCAAAUCCUGAUCAAACGCAUGAUGAUUAAGUGUGCUGACGUGGCCAACCCAUGCCGCCCCUUGGACCUGUGCAUUGAAUGGGCUGGGAGGAUCUCUGAGGAGUAUUUUGCACAGACUGAUGAAGAGAAGAGACAGGGACUACCUGUGGUGAUGCCAGUGUUUGACCGGAAUACCUGUAGCAUCCCCAAGUCUCAGAUCUCUUUCAUUGACUACUUCAUAACAGACAUGUUUGAUGCUUGGGAUGCCUUUGCACAUCUGCCAGCCCUGAUGCAACAUUUGGCUGACAACUACAAACACUGGAAGACACUAGAUGACCUAAAGUGCAAAAGUUUGAGGCUUCCAUCUGACAGCUAAAGCCAAGCCACAGAGGGGGCCUCUUGACCGACAAAGGACACUGUGAAUCACAGUAGCGUAAACGAGAGGCCUUCCUUUCUAAUGACAAUGACAGGUAUUGGUGAAGGAGCUAAUGUUUAAUAUUUGACCUUGAAUCAUUCAAGUCCCCAAAUUUCAUUCUUAGAAAGUUAUGUUCCAUGAAGAAAAAUAUAUGUUCUUUUGAAUACUUAAUGACAGAACAAAUACUUGGCAAACUCCUUUGCUCUGCUGUCAUCCUGUGUACCCUUGUCAAUCCAUGGAGCUGGUUCACUGUAACUAGCAGGCCACAGGAAGCAAAGCCUUGGUGCCUGUGAGCUCAUCUCCCAGGAUGGUGACUAAGUAGCUUAGCUAGUGAUCAGCUCAUCCUUUACCAUAAAAGUCAUCAUUGCUGUUUAGCUUGACUGUUUUCCUCAAGAACAUCGAUCUGAAGGAUUCAUAAGGAGCUUAUCUGAACAGAUUUAUCUAAGAAAAAAAAAAAACGACAUAAAAUAAGUGAAACAACUAGGACCAAAUUACAGAUAAACUAGUUAGCUUCACAGCCUCUAUGGCUACAUGGUUCUUCUGGCCGAUGGUAUGACACCUAAGUUAGAACACAGCCUUGGCUGGUGGGUGCCCUCUCUAGACUGGUAUCAGCAGCCUGUGUAACCCCUUUCCUGUAAAAGGGGUUCAUCUUAACAAAGUCAUCCAUGAUGAGGGAAAAAGUGGCAUUUCAUUUUUGGGGAAUCCAUGAGCUUCCUUUAUUUCUGGCUCACAGAGGCAGCCACGAGGCACUACACCAAGUAUUAUAUAAAAGCCAUUAAAUUUGAAUGCCCUUGGACAAGCUUUUCUUAAAAAAAAAAAAAAAAAGUUUAUAUACAUGUUUAAAAUUUUUAUUAAAAUCCAAAUUUUCUGGGUGUAAGCCCAUGCAGUAUGUUGUGCCAUGCACCAUCUAUACGUAAUAUUUUGGGAGGGGAUAGGGGAAGUUUCAAGGUUCAGAUAUUUUUAACCAGUCUAUAUUUGAAAUCAUGCCAUUAGCUUUAACAAUGUUAAAAUUGUGUGGUGUAAAUAUAUCAGAAAAUAGGCAUAUGGGGAGGCAGUAAAUACUAUUUUAAGCUAUUAAUUGUAUGCUAAAAGCUUCUAAAGCACAAGUGCAUAUUUUUAUACUGCUCUUUUCACAACUCCCUGUGAUCUACAUAAAGUCAGACUCGAGAUUUUCCUUUCUCUUUUACCAGCUGAUCCUUCCUAUGUAUUAUAAAUAUUAGACUCCGUAAACAAACUUCAUUUUUCUUUCUCUGUACUUCAUGCUGCAUUUUUAAAAGGUAUAAACAAACAGAGACUGAAUUAAUUGAAUCAGUAAUUACUUUUUUCCAAUACAAAUUGGAAUGCAGAAUACUUGGAACUUGUACAUGGGGAAAAAAUGACUUAUCACUACAUAAUGUGCCAAUGUUUUUUUCUAUGUUUUGUACCAAAAAUGGAAAAAUAUGACAAUUCCAUGCAAAGAAAUGUAUCUAAAUUAUUUUUGUUAGAUGAUAAGAGAACUUGCUUGGUCAGGACAGCAGCCAGCUUUGUAUUGUAAUGCUAUAUUAUGUAAAUGUGAUGAAAAUGUUUUUGUGAAGUACUUGUAACUAAAUUCCUACAGCCAUUUUUCACUCCCAACAGCUGUUUUUAUUUUACCUCUUUGGCCUAAAGUUUUCAUAAUUUCAAA